AGACACGUGCUGGGGCGGGCAGGCGAGCGCCUCAGUCUGGUCGCCUGGCGGUGCCUCCGGCCCCAACGCGCCCGGGCCGCCGCGGGCCGCGCGCGCCGAUGCCCGGCUGAGUCACUGGCAGGGCAGCGCGCGUGUGGGAAGGGGCGGAGGGAGUGCGGCCGGCGGGCGGGCGGGGCGCUGGGCUCAGCCCGGCCGCAGGUGACCCGGAGGCCCUCGCCGCCCGCGGCGCCCCGAGCGCUUUGUGAGCAGAUGCGGAGCCGAGUGGAGGGCGCGAGCCAGAUGCGGGGCGACAGCUGACUUGCUGAGAGGAGGCGGGGAGGCGCGGAGCGCGCGUGUGGUCCUUGCGCCGCUGACUUCUCCACUGGUUCCUGGGCACCGAAAGAUAAACCUCUCAUAAUGAAGGCCCCCGCUGUGCUUGCACCUGGCAUCCUCGUGCUCCUGUUUACCUUGGUGCAGAGGAGCAAUGGGGAGUGUAAAGAGGCACUAGCAAAGUCCGAGAUGAAUGUGAAUAUGAAGUAUCAGCUUCCCAACUUCACCGCGGAAACACCCAUCCAGAAUGUCAUUCUACAUGAGCAUCACAUUUUCCUUGGUGCCACUAACUACAUUUAUGUUUUAAAUGAGGAAGACCUUCAGAAGGUUGCUGAGUACAAGACUGGGCCUGUGCUGGAACACCCAGAUUGUUUCCCAUGUCAGGACUGCAGCAGCAAAGCCAAUUUAUCAGGAGGUGUUUGGAAAGAUAACAUCAACAUGGCUCUAGUUGUCGACACCUACUAUGAUGAUCAACUCAUUAGCUGUGGCAGCGUCAACAGAGGGACCUGCCAGCGACAUGUCUUUCCCCACAAUCAUACUGCUGACAUACAGUCGGAGGUUCACUGCAUAUUCUCCCCACAGAUAGAAGAGCCCAGCCAGUGUCCUGACUGUGUGGUGAGCGCCCUGGGAGCCAAAGUCCUUUCAUCUGUAAAGGACCGGUUCAUCAACUUCUUUGUAGGCAAUACCAUAAAUUCUUCUUAUUUCCCAGAUCAUCCAUUGCAUUCGAUAUCAGUGAGAAGGCUAAAGGAAACGAAAGAUGGUUUUAUGUUUUUGACGGACCAGUCCUACAUUGAUGUUUUACCUGAGUUCAGAGAUUCUUACCCCAUUAAGUAUGUCCAUGCCUUUGAAAGCAACAAUUUUAUUUACUUCUUGACGGUCCAAAGGGAAACUCUAGAUGCUCAGACUUUUCACACAAGAAUAAUCAGGUUCUGUUCCAUAAACUCUGGAUUGCAUUCCUACAUGGAAAUGCCUCUGGAGUGUAUUCUCACAGAAAAGAGAAAAAAGAGAUCCACAAAGAAGGAAGUGUUUAAUAUACUUCAGGCUGCGUAUGUCAGCAAGCCUGGGGCCCAGCUUGCUAGACAAAUAGGAGCCAGCCUGAAUGAUGACAUUCUUUUCGGGGUGUUCGCACAAAGCAAGCCAGAUUCUGCCGAACCAAUGGAUCGAUCUGCCAUGUGUGCAUUCCCUAUCAAAUAUGUCAACGACUUCUUCAACAAGAUCGUCAACAAAAACAAUGUGAGAUGUCUCCAGCAUUUUUACGGACCCAAUCAUGAGCACUGCUUUAAUAGGACACUUCUGAGAAAUUCAUCAGGCUGUGAAGCGCGCCGUGAUGAAUAUCGAACAGAGUUUACCACAGCUUUGCAGCGCGUUGACUUAUUCAUGGGUCAAUUCAGCGAAGUCCUCUUAACAUCUAUAUCCACCUUCAUUAAAGGAGACCUCACCAUAGCUAAUCUUGGGACAUCAGAGGGUCGCUUCAUGCAGGUUGUGGUUUCUCGAUCAGGACCAUCAACCCCUCAUGUGAAUUUUCUCCUGGACUCCCAUCCAGUGUCUCCAGAAGUGAUUGUGGAGCAUACAUUAAACCAAAAUGGCUACACACUGGUUAUCACUGGGAAGAAGAUCACGAAGAUCCCAUUGAAUGGCUUGGGCUGCAGACAUUUCCAGUCCUGCAGUCAAUGCCUCUCUGCCCCACCCUUUGUUCAGUGUGGCUGGUGCCACGACAAAUGUGUGCGAUCGGAGGAAUGCCUGAGCGGGACAUGGACUCAACAGAUCUGUCUGCCUGCAAUCUACAAGGUUUUCCCAAAUAGUGCACCCCUUGAAGGAGGGACAAGGCUGACCAUAUGUGGCUGGGACUUUGGAUUUCGGAGGAAUAAUAAAUUUGAUUUAAAGAAAACUAGAGUUCUCCUUGGAAAUGAGAGCUGCACCUUGACUUUAAGUGAGAGCACGAUGAAUACAUUGAAAUGCACAGUUGGUCCUGCCAUGAAUAAGCAUUUCAAUAUGUCCAUAAUUAUUUCAAAUGGCCACGGGACAACACAAUACAGUACAUUCUCCUAUGUGGAUCCUGUAAUAACAAGUAUUUCGCCGAAAUACGGUCCUAUGGCUGGUGGCACUUUACUUACUUUAACUGGAAAUUACCUAAACAGUGGGAAUUCUAGACACAUUUCAAUUGGUGGAAAAACAUGUACUUUAAAAAGUGUGUCAAACAGUAUUCUUGAAUGUUAUACCCCAGCCCAAACCAUUUCAACUGAGUUUGCUGUUAAAUUGAAAAUUGACUUAGCCAACCGAGAGACAAGCAUCUUCAGUUACCGUGAAGAUCCCAUUGUCUAUGAAAUUCAUCCAACCAAAUCUUUUAUUAGUACUUGGUGGAAAGAACCUCUCAACAUUGUCAGUUUUCUAUUUUGCUUUGCCAGUGGUGGGAGCACAAUAACAGGUGUUGGGAAAAACCUGAAUUCAGUUAGUGUCCCGAGAAUGGUCAUAAAUGUGCAUGAAGCAGGAAGGAACUUUACAGUGGCAUGUCAACAUCGCUCUAAUUCAGAGAUAAUCUGUUGUACCACUCCUUCCCUGCAACAGCUGAAUCUGCAACUCCCCCUGAAAACCAAAGCCUUUUUCAUGUUAGAUGGGAUCCUUUCCAAAUACUUUGAUCUCAUUUAUGUACAUAAUCCUGUGUUUAAGCCUUUUGAAAAGCCAGUGAUGAUCUCAAUGGGCAAUGAAAAUGUACUGGAAAUUAAGGGAAAUGAUAUUGACCCUGAAGCAGUUAAAGGUGAAGUGUUAAAAGUUGGAAAUAAGAGCUGUGAGAAUAUACACUUACAUUCUGAAGCCGUUUUAUGCACGGUCCCCAAUGACCUGCUGAAAUUGAACAGCGAGCUAAAUAUAGAGUGGAAGCAAGCAAUUUCUUCAACCGUCCUUGGAAAAGUAAUAGUUCAACCAGAUCAGAAUUUCACAGGAUUGAUUGCUGGUGUUGUCUCAAUAUCAACAGCACUGUUAUUACUACUUGGGUUUUUCCUGUGGCUGAAAAAGAGAAAGCAAAUUAAAGAUCUGGGCAGUGAAUUAGUUCGCUACGAUGCAAGAGUACACACUCCUCAUUUGGAUAGGCUUGUAAGUGCCCGAAGUGUAAGCCCAACUACAGAAAUGGUUUCAAAUGAAUCUGUAGACUACCGAGCUACUUUUCCAGAAGAUCAGUUUCCUAAUUCAUCUCAGAACGGUUCAUGCCGACAAGUGCAGUAUCCUCUGACAGACAUGUCCCCCAUCCUAACUAGUGGGGACUCUGAUAUAUCCAGUCCAUUACUGCAAAAUACUGUCCACAUUGACCUCAGUGCUCUAAAUCCAGAGCUGGUCCAGGCAGUGCAGCAUGUAGUGAUUGGGCCCAGUAGCCUGAUUGUGCAUUUCAAUGAAGUCAUAGGAAGAGGGCAUUUUGGUUGUGUAUAUCAUGGGACUUUGUUGGACAAUGAUGGCAAGAAAAUUCACUGUGCUGUGAAAUCCUUGAACAGAAUCACUGACAUAGGAGAAGUUUCCCAAUUUCUGACCGAGGGAAUCAUCAUGAAAGAUUUUAGUCAUCCCAAUGUCCUCUCGCUCCUGGGAAUCUGCCUGCGAAGUGAAGGGUCUCCGCUGGUGGUCCUACCAUACAUGAAACAUGGAGAUCUUCGAAAUUUCAUUCGAAAUGAGACUCAUAAUCCAACUGUAAAAGAUCUUAUUGGCUUUGGUCUUCAAGUAGCCAAAGGCAUGAAAUAUCUUGCAAGCAAAAAGUUUGUCCACAGAGACUUGGCUGCAAGAAACUGUAUGCUGGAUGAAAAAUUCACAGUCAAGGUUGCUGAUUUUGGUCUUGCCAGAGACAUGUAUGAUAAAGAAUACUAUAGUGUACACAACAAAACAGGUGCAAAGCUGCCAGUGAAGUGGAUGGCUUUGGAAAGUCUGCAAACUCAAAAGUUUACCACCAAGUCAGAUGUGUGGUCCUUUGGCGUGCUCCUCUGGGAGCUGAUGACAAGAGGAGCCCCACCUUAUCCUGACGUAAACACCUUUGAUAUAACUGUUUACUUGUUGCAAGGGAGAAGACUCCUACAACCCGAAUACUGCCCAGACCCCUUAUAUGAAGUAAUGCUAAAAUGCUGGCACCCUAAAGCCGAAAUGCGCCCAUCCUUUUCUGAACUGGUGUCCCGGAUAUCAGCGAUCUUCUCUACUUUCAUUGGGGAGCACUAUGUCCAUGUGAACGCUACUUAUGUGAACGUAAAAUGUGUCGCUCCGUAUCCUUCUCUGUUGUCAUCAGAAGAUAACGCUGAUGAUGAGGUGGACACACGACCAGCCUCCUUCUGGGAGACAUCAUAGUGCUAGUACUAUGUCAAAGCAACAGUCCACACUUUGUCCAAUGGUUUUUUCACUGCCUGACCUUUAAAAGGCCAUCGAUAUUCUUUGCUCUUGCCAAAAUUGCACUAUUAUAGGACUUGUAUUGUUAUUUAAAUUACUGGAUUCUAAGGAAUUUCUUAUCUGACAGAGCAUCAGAACCAGAGGCUUGGUCCCACAGGCCACGGACCAAUGGCCUGCAGCCGUGACAACACUCCUGUCAUAUUGGAGUCCAAAACUUGAAUUCUGGGUUGAAUUUUUUAAAAAUCAGGUACCACUUGAUUUCAUAUGGGAAAUUGAAGCAGGAAAUAUUGAGGGCUUCUUGAUCACAGAAAACUCAGAAGAGAUAGUAAUGCUCAGGACAGGAGCGGCAGCCCCAGAACAGGCCACUCAUUUAGAAUUCUAGUGUUUCAAAACACUUUUGUGUGUUGUAUGGUCAAUAACAUUUUUCAUUACUGAUGGUGUCAUUCACCCAUUAGGUAAACAUUCCCUUUUAAAUGUUUGUUUGUUUUUUGAGACAGGAUCUCACUCUGUUGCCAGGGCUGUAGUGCAGUGGUGUGAUCAUAGCUCACUGCAACCUCCACCUCCCAGGCUCAAGCCUCCCGAAUAGCUGGGACUACAGGCGCACACCACCAUCCCCGGCUAAUUUUUGUAUUUUUUGUAGAGACGGGGUUUUGCCAUGUUGCCAAGGCUGGUUUCAAACUCCUGGACUCAAGAAAUCCACCCACCUCAGCCUCCCAAAGUGCUAGGAUUACAGGCAUGAGCCACUGCGCCCAGCCCUUAUAAAUUUUUGUAUAGACAUUCCUUUGGUUGGAAGAAUAUUUAUAGGCAAUACAGUCAAAGUUUCAAAAUAGCAUCACACAAAACAUGUUUAUAAAUGAACAGGAUGUAAUGUACAUAGAUGACAUUAAGAAAAUUUGUAUGAAAUAAUUUAGUCAUCAUGAAAUAUUUAGUUGUCAUAUAAAAACCCACUGUUUGAGAAUGAUGCUACUCUGAUCUAAUGAAUGUGAACAUGUAGAUGUUUUGUGUGUAUUUUUUUAAAUGAAAACUCAAAAUAAGACAAGUAAUUUGUUGAUAAAUAUUUUUAAAGAUAACUCAGCAUGUUUGUAAAGCAGGAUACAUUUUACUAAAAGGUUCAUUGGUUCCAAUCACAGCUCAUAGGUAGAGCAAAGAAAGGGUGGAUGGAUUGAAAAGAUUAGCCUCUGUCUCGGUGGCAGGUUCCCACCUCGCAAGCAAUUGGAAACAAAACUUUUGGGGAGUUUUAUUUUGCAUUAGGGUGUGUUUUAUGUUAAGCAAAACAUACUUUAGAAACAAAUGAAAAAGGCAAUUGAAAAUCCCAGCUAUUUCACCUAGAUGGAAUAGCCACCCUGAGCAGAACUUUGUGAUGCUUCAUUCUGUGGAAUUUUGUGCUUGCUACUGUAUAGUGCAUGUGGUGUAGGUUACUCUAACUGGUUUUGUCGACGUAAACAUUUAAAGUGUUAUAUUUUUUAUAAAAAUGUUUAUUUUUAAUGAUAUGAGAAAAAUUUUGUUAGGCCACAAAAACACUGCACUGUGAACAUUUUAGAAAAGGUAUGUCAGACUGGGAUUAAUGACAGCAUGAUUUUCAAUGACUGUAAAUUGCGAUAAGGAAAUGUACUGAUUGCCAAUACACCCCACCCUCAUUACAUCAUCAGGACUUGAAGCCAAGGGUUAACCCAGCAAGCUACAAAGAGGGUGUGUCACACUGAAACUCAAUAGUUGAGUUUGGCUGUUGUUGCAGGAAAAUGAUUAUAACUAAAAGCUCUCUGAUAGUGCAGAGACUUACCAGAAGACACAAGGAAUUGUACUGAAGAGCUAUUACAAUCCAAAUAUUGCCGUUUCAUAAAUGUAAUAAGUAAUACUAAUUCACAGAGUAUUGUAAAUGGUGGAUGACAAAAGAAAAUCUGCUCUGUGGAAAGAAAGAACUGUCUCUACCAGGGUCAAGAGCAUGAACGCAUCAAUAGAAAGAACUCGGGGAAACAUCCCAUCAACAGGACUACACACUUGUAUAUACAUUCUUGAGAACACUGCAAUGUGAAAAUCACGUUUGCUAUUUAUAAACUUGUCCUUAGAUUAAUGUGUCUGGACAGAUUGUGGGAGUAAGUGAUUCUUCUAAGAAUUAGAUACUUGUCACUGCCUAUACCUGCAGCUGAACUGAAUGGUACUUCGUAUGUUAAUAGUUGUUCUGAUAAAUCAUGCAAUUAAAGUAAAGUGAUGCAA